GGGUCUGAGGUUUGGUGACUGCGGGGCAGGCCGGGGGCAGCUGUCUGUCUGGCUCUUUUUGACAGCCCCCAGUGCGAAAGGCUGCCAGCAUGUCAUCAGUGAGCCCCAUCCAGAUCCCCAGUCGCCUCCCGCUGCUGCUCACCCACGAGGGCGUCCUGCUGCCCGGCUCCACCAUGCGCACCAGCGUGGACUCGGCCCGCAACCUGCAGCUGGUGCGGAGCCGCCUUCUGAAGGGCACGUCGCUGCAAAGCACCAUCCUGGGCGUCAUCCCCAACACGCCUGACCCCGCCAGCGACGCGCAGGACCUGCCGCCGCUGCACAGGAUUGGCACAGCUGCACUGGCCGUUCAGGUUGUGGGCAGUAACUGGCCCAAGCCCCACUACACUCUGUUGAUUACAGGCCUAUGCCGUUUCCAGAUUGUACAGGUCUUAAAAGAGAAGCCAUAUCCCAUUGCUGAAGUGGAGCAGUUGGACCGACUUGAGGAGUUUCCCAACACCUGUAAAAUGAGGGAGGAGCUAGGAGAACUAUCAGAGCAGUUUUACAAAUAUGCAGUACAAUUGGUUGAAAUGUUGGAUAUGUCUGUCCCUGCAGUUGCUAAAUUGAGACGUCUUUUAGAUAGUCUUCCAAGGGAAGCUUUACCAGACAUCUUGACAUCAAUUAUCCGAACAAGCAACAAAGAGAAACUCCAGAUUUUAGAUGCUGUGAGCCUAGAGGAGCGGUUCAAGAUGACUAUACCACUGCUUGUCAGACAAAUUGAAGGCCUGAAAUUGCUUCAAAAAACCAGAAAACCCAAGCAAGAUGAUGAUAAGAGGGUUAUAGCAAUACGCCCUAUUAGGAGAAUUACACAUAUCUCAGGUACUUUAGAAGAUGAAGAUGAAGAUGAAGAUAAUGAUGACAUUGUCAUGCUAGAGAAAAAAAUACGAACAUCUAGUAUGCCAGAGCAGGCCCAUAAAGUCUGUGUCAAAGAGAUAAAGAGACUCAAAAAAAUGCCUCAGUCAAUGCCAGAAUAUGCUCUGACUAGAAAUUAUUUGGAACUUAUGGUAGAACUUCCUUGGAACAAAAGUACAACUGACCGCCUGGACAUUAGGGCAGCCCGGAUUCUUCUGGAUAAUGACCAUUACGCCAUGGAAAAAUUGAAGAAAAGAGUACUGGAAUACUUGGCUGUCAGACAGCUCAAAAAUAACCUGAAGGGCCCAAUCCUAUGCUUUGUUGGCCCUCCUGGAGUUGGUAAAACAAGUGUGGGAAGAUCAGUGGCCAAGACUCUAGGUCGAGAGUUCCACAGGAUUGCACUUGGAGGAGUAUGUGAUCAGUCUGACAUUCGAGGACACAGGCGCACCUAUGUUGGCAGCAUGCCUGGUCGCAUCAUCAACGGCUUGAAGACUGUGGGAGUGAACAACCCAGUGUUCCUAUUAGAUGAGGUUGACAAACUGGGAAAAAGUCUACAGGGUGAUCCAGCAGCAGCUCUGCUUGAGGUGUUGGAUCCUGAACAAAACCAUAACUUCACAGAUCAUUAUCUAAAUGUGGCCUUUGACCUUUCUCAAGUUCUUUUUAUAGCUACUGCCAACACCACUGCUACCAUUCCAGCUGCCUUGUUGGACAGAAUGGAGAUCAUUCAGGUUCCAGGUUAUACACAGGAGGAGAAGAUAGAGAUUGCCCAUAGGCACUUGAUCCCCAAGCAGCUGGAACAACAUGGGCUGACUCCACAGCAGAUUCAGAUACCCCAGGUCACCACUCUUGACAUCAUCACCAGGUAUACCAGAGAGGCAGGGGUUCGUUCUCUGGAUAGAAAACUUGGGGCCAUUUGCCGAGCUGUGGCCGUGAAGGUGGCAGAAGGACAGCAUAAGGAAGCCAAGUUGGACCGUUCUGAUGUGACUGAGAGAGAAGGUUGCAGAGAACACAUCUUAGAAGAUGAAAAACCUGAAUCUAUCAGUGACACUACUGACUUGGCUCUACCACCUGAAAUGCCGAUUUUGAUUGAUUUCCAUGCUCUGAAAGACAUCCUUGGGCCCCCGAUGUAUGAAAUGGAGAUAGCAUCUUAGAAUGGAAGAUGUGGUGUGUCACAUGCGUGCGUGCGGAGAGACCACCAAACAGGCUUUGUGUGAGCAACAAGGCUGUUAUUUCACCUGGGUACAGAUUGAAAAAUGAUGGAUUAGUUCAUUCUUGCAUUCCUAUAAAGAAAUACCUGAAACCAGGCACAGUGGCUCACGCCUGUAAAUCCCAGCGCUUUGGGAGGCCAAGGUGGGCGGAUCGCUUGAGUUCGAGACCAACCUGGGCAGCAAAGUGAGACCUGGUCUCUACAAAAAAUACAAAAUAUUACCCGGAAGGCUGAGGUGGGAUCCACCUGAGCCCAGAAGGUUGAGGCUGCAGUGAGCUGUGAUCACACCAUUGCACUCUAGCCUAAGUGACAGAGUGAAAACUCUGUCUCAAAAAAAACAAAGAACCACCUGAGACUGGGUAAUUUAUAAAGAAAAGAGGUUUAAUUGGCUCACGGUUCUGAAGGUUCUAAAGGAAGCAUAGCUCCAGCAUUAGGCCAGGUGCAUUGGCUCACACCUGUAAUCCCAGCACUUUGGGAGGCCAAGGGCAGGCGGAUCAUGAGGUCAGGAUUUCGAGACCAGCCUGGCCAAUAUGGUGAAACCCUGUCUCUACUAAAAAUACAAAAUUAGCUGGGCGUGGUGGCGCACACCUGUAGUCUCAGCUACUCGAGAGGCCGAGGCAGAAGAAUCACUUGAACCCAGGAGGCGGAGGUUGCAAUGAGCUGAGAUCGUGCCACUGCACUCCAGCUUGGGACACAGAGUGAGACUCCAUCUCAAAAAUAAAUAAAUAAAUAAAUAAAUAAAUAGGUCCAGCAUCAGCUUCUGGGGAGGCCUCAGGAAACUUACAGCCUUGGCAGAAAGUGAAGGGGGAGCCGGCAUGUCAUGUGGCCAGAGCAGGAGCAAGAGUGCAGGAGGGGAGGUGGCCACAUGCUUUUAAACAACCACCUCCCACAAGAACUCACUCACUAUUGCGAGGACGACAGUACCAAGGGGAUGGGGCUAAACCAUUCAUGAGAAAUUUCCCUCCGUGAUCCAGUCACCUCCCACCAGGCCCCACCUCCAGCACUGAGGAUUAUAGUUCAACAUGAGAUUUGGUGGAGACACAGAUCCAAACCAUAUCAAAUGGGUUCUAGGAACUUAGCCUAGAUUUCAGAUUUAGGAACAGUAUCAUAGGUCACCUUUUCAAAAUACAUAAAGUUUCCUACAGAAACAAUAUCAAUUAAGUGCAUGUUUUAAAAAUAAAAAUAAAGGUUACUACAAAAAAAGUGGGGAGGAGCAGGAGUGGGUGCAGGUGUCCCCAGGAAGCCUAGGCAUAGCUCACACUGCAUGUGCUAUCACGGCAAGACUCAGAACUGCCCCGAAUCCGAGGAGGGGCCAUGCGAGUAGGUGGGCCUAGGCACCUCCUCAGUCACUGGCUGUGCCCUUUCACUCUGUCACUGGGAGACAGAAUCCUGAGUUUUCUGCUUCAGGGAGCCUGCAUGGAAAGAGUAGGUCACUGCCGGAAAUCAGGCUAGUUUUAGCAAAAGGAACGGACAUUAGGCACCUCCAAAGGGACAAAGGACCAAUAUACCUGGUUGGGGACAGGAUUCUGUCAUUUGAUUAUUCCUGACUCAUGUUUUCAUGAGGUAGUCCCCCACCUCAUAUAAAAGCCUCAGUGUUGGCUUCUGACCAUGGUGUAUGAAAAGCCCUUGUCUAAAGGUUACUGCCCUGAGAAAAUAAUAAAGGAAGAAGAGGAUAGACAUGAAGACACUUUAAAGCCUCCUGAAUAGAAUGCAUCCAGAAGCGAAUUCCAGGAGAUUCUGUCAUCAUGCUUGCCUUUCAAGCAAACAAAAUUAGCUGCUAGAACUGAGAAAGAGUGUAAACACCAACUAAAUGCCUCAAAGAAUCAUGGUAGUAAAUUACUUCUCCAUGUUGCUCCAUAUAAACCUGCUGUGCCACCUGUUGAAGGCAGCACUGAUGCUGCAUGUUCAGUCUGGUCCAAGGCCCCAACAGGAAUCCGUUGUGCCAAGAAAAGGCCCUACUGGAAGGAUUGGAGAGCAGCUGGUUCUCAGCAAUGCAAGCAUCAGGCCAGGCUGGGGCUGCUUAAUGCUGCUUAAGAGAUGACAGUGGUGGACCCCAACACCUCUCCAAGGGAUGUAGAAUCUGCUUUUCCCAUUUCUGAAUGCUACUGAAACAAAUCUACAACUAGAAAAAUCAAAUAUUCAUGAAUUCAAGACUUGGGAUCUCAGUACUAAGACUUUAAAGAAGUUGCCAGAUGGAUCGCUUCUGUGGUGACAGCCCUGGCAGGAGCAUUCAAGUGCUCUAUGAGCUACAAAAGAAACCAGUUGAUGGUGUGAACACCACUACAGAGCAACCUGCACACCACAGCAAUUUGACAGCUCAGGUUCUGUGUCUCAUGUGGCACCGUGCUUGUCCUUGGAAAGAAGGCCUACAAAAUUCUUCAUAUCUCCAUUCCUUGACAUCUGCUGGCAAACUCCCACUCAUAUUUUAAGACUCAGCCUCUCCUGUGACACCUGUGUCUUCUCUCCAAACAGGGAGGGACGCUUGCCUCUUCAGAGCUCCCCACACUGGAGUAUAACUGCUCCUGUGUCUGAUGCCCUUAGUCUCAGUGCCAGGAGGUAUUCAUGCUUAUGUCCCCAUGGCCUGUAACAGAGCCUGCAUCAGGAUGCUUGGUAAAGGACUGUUGAAUGAAUGUCAAAUAUGGGUCCCUCUGAUGGGUCUAUACGUGUUGAUCUAGGAUUGGAAGGGUCACAAAGAGUUGUGCAUGCUUACAAUUUCAAUCAAAUAUCACUAUUUUUAGUUAAGAGGGAAGAGUAGUGUGAAAUUGGCAAUAAUUAGAUACUCCAAAUGUUCUUUAAAAACUAAUAGCAUUGAUGUAUUAAGAAUGCAAUCAGCCGGGCACAGCAGCUCACACCUGUAAUCCCAGCACUUUGGGAGGCUGAGGCAGGUGGAUCAUGAGGUCAGGAGUUCGAGACCAGCCUGGCCAAGAUUGUGAAACCCCCGUCUCUACUAAAAAUACAAAAAUUAGCCGGGCAUGGUGACGCACACCUGUAGUCCCAGCUACUUGGGAGGCUGAGGCAGGAGAAUUGCUUGAACCCAGGAGGUGGAGGUUGCAGUGAGCCCAGAUCGUGCCAUUGCACUCCAGCCUGGGUGACGAGCGAAACUCAGUCUAAAAAAAAAAAGAAUGCAAUCAUACAUUAGAAGACACAUUCUGUUUUAGAUUUUUACUUAAAUAUUUUAAAUACUUCCUUAAUCUGCAUAUUUACCUUAUUGAUAGAUUUCAGAAGAAAUUGAUCAUUUCAUGGAACAAGAUUUAUUAGACACAUAAGGAAAGUGAAUCAUAACAACUGUACAGGUGGGAAAUUGAACAACAAAAAUGACCCUGAGAUACCCACAUUCUACUUUGGCAUAUAGUGGGAAAAACAUUCUAGACUUCAAGUCUAGGCCUAUCUUGGCUAAUGUAACCGAUGACUUCACAAACCAUUUAUGGGACUAGAAGCUGAAAGGAAAGUACUGGUGGAUAAACAUCAUAUUGAAAUUAUGUUGAGUCACUUAUUUGCUAUAAAACACAAAUUGUUUUGUGUAAAGGGGUUAAGAUGGCUGGAAAACUGUCUCCACUCAAGAGCAAGAAAGCAGCAUGUGUCUUACCCUGUACCUUCAUUUUUACUUGUACUUCAUAAUUUCUGAGGGAGAAAUACGUGGAAACCAGAUGCUUGAUAUAGUUUCAGAACACGUCCUUAAAGAAUAUGACUCCAAGUCUAAGAAUUGUAGGUCCUUUGCUUCUUAGAUAACUACUGUUAGCCUUGAUCACAGAGAUUCCAGGUUUAAUAACUUCAGUUCUCCCCACUGUGUAUAUAGAUGUUAAGUUACACAGAUUUGGCAUUAUUCCCAUUUUCAGGUUAAUAUCAGAACACUUGUUAUCAAGUCAGGAUAGUAAUUGUGAGCCUAGAUGCUCUAGGUUUGGCCAUACGUGGUUAUCUACACCACCAACUGUUCCAAUUAACAAUUUACCAGUUGCUUCUACCCAAAGUACCAAGACUCCAGCAAAUGGGGAAUAUUGGAAACUGGCUUGGCUUCUUGAAGCAACAUGGUAAUCAAUAAGAAUCUUGGCUGGGCAUGGUGGCUCAUGCCUGCAGUCCCAGCACUUUAGGAGGCCAAGAUGGAAAGAUGGGAAGAUCGCUCAAGCCCAGGAGUUCAAGACCAGCCUGGGCGACAUCGUGAAACCCCAUCUCUACAAAAAAAUACAAAAAUUAGCUGGGUAUGGUCGUGGGUGCCUGUAGUCCCAGCUGCUGGGGAGCUGAGGUGGGAGAUCACCUGAGCCCAGGAGGCAGUUGCAGUGAGCCAAGAUUGCACCACUGCACUCCAGCCUGGGUGACAGAGUGAGACUCUGUCUCAAAACAAACAAAACAACAAUCUGGCUGGGCGCGGUCGCUAAUGUCUGUAAUCCCAACACUUUGGGAGGCUGAGGAGGCAGAUCACUUGAGGUCAGGAAUUCGAGACCAGCCUGGCCAACAUGGUGAAACCCGUCUCUAUUAAAAAUACAAAAAUUAGCCGGGCAUGGUGGCACACACCUGUAAUCCCAGCUACUUGGGAGGCUGAGGCAAGAGAAUUGCUUGAACCAGGAGGCAGAGGUUGCAGUGAGCUGAGAUCAUGCCUCUGCACUCCAGCCUGAGCUACAGAGCGAGACUCUGUCUCAAAAAAACAAAAAACAAAAACAAGAAGAAUCUUACUACUGCUUCUUCGGGGAUACUUUUGGUAUUAUUUUGACAAAUGAAUUGUGAGGAUUCAAAUAUAAGAAAGGGAUUAUUCUUGGUAGAGUUAACAAAAUUGUACCAAAUGACUUUUUGUGUUAAACACGAUUCAUUCACCCAACCCUAGAAAGGAGCCUGAAUGAAGUCUAAUUUGGGUGACAGAUUCCCACACAAAUUAGAUGUAUGUCAUUCAGGUAUAGAGAAUUGAUUUUAUAUUAGAAAAAACAAACCUUGUAAACAGUUUUAUAAAUAACUGUUUCAUGAUUUUCCUUAAGUAGUACUGAUCUCUUACAUAUAGAUCGUUUGUGUCUUUCGCCUCAAGUUAGUAUAGAACAGGGCAAGUGGCAAAGCUCGAGGAAAGUGUGACCUGAGGUACAUGCUGUCAGCUUGAUGCUGGAGUUUGGCCUCUCAAAUCUCUAACCUGUUAAAUGAAGUUAAUUAGGAUUAAUUUUUUUUAAUGUAUGUUUACUACUGAAAAUAAGUGCUCGGCCAGACGCAGAGGCUCACGCCUGUAAUCCCAGCACUUUGGGAGGCCGAGGCUGGCAGAUCACCUGAAGUCAGGAGUUUGAGACCAGCCUGGCCAACAUGGCGAAACACUGUCUCUAUUAAAAAUACAAAAAUUAGCUGGGUGUGGUGAUACAUGCCUGUAAUCCCAGCUACUCGGAGCCUGAGGCAGGAGAACUGCUUGAACCCAGGAGGCGGAGGUUGCAUUGAGCCAAGAUUGUGCCAUUGCACUCCAGCCCAGGCGACAGAGUGAGACUCAUGUCUCAAAAAAAAAAAAAAAAAAAAGAGGAAAAGAAGUGCCCAAUAGCUUCAAUGGAUGCCACAUAAUUUUGGAAUAAUUUUUACAAUCAGGAAUUUCAUUGUCCAAGCCCCUUAGAAAAAGAAGCAACCCAGCCCCAUACCCAGAAAGUCAAGCUGUAUAGUGCUGUUCCUUAGUGAGACGGUCAACUCUCAGUAGAAAAAUCUCCUGUUUGGAUUAGUGCUUAGUUGACCUAUUGUGUUCAGUUCCUCUAACAUGAGUAACUUCUAUUGGAUAGGAAAUUUUGAAGCUCAAAGGGUGUAAUGAGAGUUAACAUUACUGAUUUUCCACUGUUACUUUUUAGUGUUUUCAUAACUUGGAUGUGUUAACCUAUGGCCCAUCAACUAUGCUCCUAGUCUCAGGUGACAACAUGUUCAAUUUAAGAUGGCAGGCAGUACAGUGGACCUCUCUCAUCCCAUGGGAAGGAACCCAGGAUGUUUAUUAUGUAGUAUUGUAUAGUCUCUGCAGCAGUAAUAGAGAAAGUUAAAGGUAAGCGGUGGAGAAGUAAAAUCUAGAGUUUCUAAUAUAACCCUUCUCACUUUUCUUUUCAAAAAAAAUAAGAGGGUCUCACCAUGUUGCCCACACUGGUCUCUAUCGAACUCCUGGGCUCAAGCGAUCCUGUCGUCUCAGCCUCCCAAAGUGCUAGGAUUACAGGCAUGAGCCACUCUGCAUGGCCAAGCUCACUCUUCUUAAAGGUCUGCUAGUAAGAGGGUUUCUACUUUUUGAAACAAAUUCAUGAUUACCUAAAAUGAAGCUAGGUUAUGAAGUAUAUAUAAAUAUGCAGCCCAAUAGGCUGGGUGUGGUGGCUCACACCUGUAAUCCCAGCACUUUGGG